ACAAGCCGGCGGCCAGAGCCCCAGACCACACAGACCGUGCGCUCCUCCGCCCUCCCGGCGCCGCCGGCCUCGCCCAUGUCUCAGUACGCCCCUAGCCCGGACUUCAAGAGGGCUUUGGACAGCAGUCCCGAGGCCAACACUGAAGAUGACAAGACCGAGGAGGACGUGCCCAUGCCCAAGAACUACCUGUGGCUCACCAUCGUCUCGUGUUUUUGCCCUGCGUACCCCAUCAACAUCGUGGCUUUGGUCUUUUCCAUCAUGUCUCUGAACAGCUACAACGAUGGAGACUACGAAGGAGCCAGGCGGCUUGGGCGGAAUGCUAAGUGGGUAGCCAUCGCCUCCAUCAUCAUUGGCCUUCUCAUCAUCGGCAUUUCUUGUGCAGUUCACUUCACAAGGAAAGGGGCUGGAAAAUCUGACAUUAGAGGAGUCGAAGCCUGAAGAUGAGCCCAAAACCCAUGAAUCUUGCCUGAGGAACCAGCGGUCAGUGGGCUGUGAGCGUGGAGGAUGGACCUCAUCCACACACACCCCAAAGGAGUUUCUAAGGAAUGGAUCCUUGACUUCAGACUGUGAGAUCUUUUCCUCCAGGACUCUCCAGAGGCAGGUCCCUGGCAAAUGAACAAGAAAAAAAAAAAAAAAAAGUCCAAAAUUUAGGCAAUCCAAGCUGCACAGCCGGAUCAGCCAAAGUCAUUGAUUUGUAAAAAUGAAAAGAAAACAGAAAAAAGAAAAAUGAAGUCUCACUGUCUCAGUUUAGCGAAUCCCGUUGUGUCCACUCCUGUCCUCCAGAGGCGAGCCUCAGGAAAUCACAUAACUUUUCACUGAGGGGAUCCAGGGGGUCUCCAUAUAGGGGGAGAUGGAGGUUUCUAGGAAGAGCAGCAGGUGCUGGUAUUUACAAUGUUGAGCACAAACAUUUGCAGCAUGUUUAAAAUUGUCUAGUAGAGUUCAAGUUGUGGAUUUGCUUUUCCUUUUAUUCUUAUAACCUUCAGUAACUCCUCCUCUGGGAGUCAGCACUCCCAUGCCCAGAGUUCACCCAUCUGGUCAUCAAACACUCAAAGAAGGGGCUUUUCUGGCCUUUUGUCUUGAUGCUUAUAUUUCCAAAUAGGCCCCCUCCCUUGCUUGCAUCCACGUUGGUCAACUUGACCAAAACCUCACUCUUCACUCAAACAGGCUCUGAGAAUGGACUUAGUGGCCAAUUCUAGGUACAUGAGCACUUCCUGUAUCCCAGUUUUGGGAAUAAACUGGCUGUAUUUAUAGAAUGUGCUUUUUUUUUUUCAAUUUCUCACUCUCUCUCCUAUCUCUAGCAAGUCUCAGGCAAGAUCUUUGAUUUUCCUGGAUGCCACCUGGAAAUGCCACCCAUUGUGUUUCUUUUCUGUCAAAUGUAAACCCUUUAGAUGUGAAUGUACUGGUUUAAUGAUGCCAUUAUUCUGCCUGCCAGAACGCAGUAACCCAGUGUCUCACAGAGCACAAGGGGUGUGCCACUGGUGGUACACAAGAUAAUUUUUAAGUAGUUUCUAGGAACAACAUUAAGUAAUACCAAAUCACAAAGAAUGUUUCCCCUUUUCUAUUCUUUUUUCAUCCUGAUUACAGCAAGGAAAAAGUCUCUGUUUAGUGCUAGCAGGUCCUUUACACCUUUCAGACACUAUGGCUCUUUUCCCUUUUUAGCAAAGAAAGAGCAGGCCUCAGAGUCUUCUGUCUAGAUAGAAUUUAAUGAUAUUGUUUUGUGUCAUGGUAUUUAUUUUAUUUAUUACCUUCCAUUUACAGCUUCCCACAGUGGGGGAUGUGACAUAUUGUUUCUGUUCAAAUAAAUUAAGAAAAACAAGAGAACUCAAGAAAAUAUCAAGUAAUUAACACACCAGAUAAGUAUAUGUGGCAAAAGUCACUUCAAAGAAUUAAUGUCAGAAAGAUGGUGAUAAUGAAGCAAAAGAAAGGCAGAUUAUGCUGGCCGGGCGUGGUGGCUCACGCCUGUAAUCCCAGCAAUUUGAGAGGCUGAGAUCACUUAAGGUCAGGAGUUUGAGACCAGCCUGACCAACAUGGUGAAACUCCAUCUCUACUAAAAAUACAAAAAUUAGCCAGGCGUGGUGGUGCAUGCCUGUAAUCCCAGCUAAUAGAGAGGCUGAGGCAGGAGAAUCACUUGAAUCCAGAAGGCGGAGGUUGCCGUGAGCUGAGACUGUGCCACUACACUCCAGCCCGGGGUGACAGAGCAAGACUCCAUCUCAAAAAAAAAAGAAAAGAAAACGAAAGAAAAAGAAAAAAGAAAGGCAGAUUAUUCUAAUUGAAUGAAUAAGAGGCUGAGAGUCAAUACCUAGUUCCAACGCCCUUUUGUUUUUGCAGGGUUUUUAUUGGCCACUAACUAGCUAUGCAAGCUGAUUUUAGGCAAGUUUCAUAGCCUCUCUGUGCCUAAAAUUCCUUCACCUGCAAAAUGGGGAUAAGAAUGCCUGCCUACUUACCUCACAGUGCUGUUAUGAGAAUUAAUUGUUGUAAUAGUUGUGACUAACCAUUGGCGGGGAGAAUUCUAAGUACUAUACCAAUACAAAUUUCAGCAUUUUUUCAUAUACUGAACCCUAGCAAAAAAAAAAAAAAUUCUGAUGAACAUCAGAUUCAACCUGUCAUUUUACCCGGAUGUUGUGAUGAGCCAGCACUUGUCCCAGGAGGACGUUGAAUCAGGGACACGAAAUCUCAGCACACAGAGAUUCUAGCAUCAUUCCAAUAGAUUGGACCCUGAUUUCUGUUUCUGACAUCCUGUUUUUUGUUUGUGCGUGUUUGGGUCCCUGGUCUUUUACCCAAAUCAAAUGAAAAGUGUUGCUCAGAGGCAGAAUAAAAAUGGUUUUAAGUAAGCCUGUGUA